AAAUUCCGGCGACAGCAGGGCAAAACAGGAGCUGAUUCGAGCUGGCAGAGCUGGGCCAUGGAACCGGUAGAGACCUGGACCCCCGGAAAGGUGGCAACUUGGCUGAGAGGUCUUGACGACUCCCUGCAGGACUAUCCCUUUGAGGACUGGCAGCUGCCUGGCAAGAACCUGCUCCAGCUCUGCCCCCAAAGCCUCGAGGCUCUGGCUGUGCGGUCUCUGGGACACCAGGAGCUCAUCCUGGGCGGGGUGGAACAGCUCCAGGCCCUGAGCUCCAGGCUACAGACAGAGAACCUGCAAAGCCUGACAGAGGGACUUCUGGGGGCAACCCAUGACUUCCAGAGCAUAGUCCAAGGCUGCCUGGGGGACUGUGCCAAGACCCCUAUUGAUGUCCUCUGUGCAGCUGUGGAGCUGUUGCAUGAAGCUGACGCCCUCCUCUUCUGGCUCAGCAGGUACCUCUUCUCCCACUUAAAUGAUUUCUCAGCAUGCCAGGAGAUCCGAGACUUGUUGGAGGAGCUGAGCCAGGUCUUGCAUGAGGAUGGUCCAGCGGCUGAGAAGGAGGGCACAGUCCUGAGGAUCUGCAGCCACGUGGCUGGGAUCUGCCACAACAUCCUGGUCUGCUGCCCCAAGGAGCUGCUGGAACAGAAGGCCGUGCUCGAGCAGGUGCAGCUGGACAGUCCAUUGGGCCUAGAAAUUCACACCACCAGCAAUUGCCAGCACUUUGUGUCCCAAGUGGACACCCAGGUUCCCACUGACUCCCGACUGCAGAUCCAGCCUGGAGACGAGGUUGUCCAGAUCAACGAGCAGGUGGUGGUGCGUGAGGAGAGGGACAUGGUGGGAUGGCCCCGUAAGAACAUGGUGAGGGAACUGCUGCGGGAGCCAGCCGGACUCAGCUUAGUGCUGAAGAAGAUCCCGAUACCGGAGACCCCCCCACAGACGCCCCCUCAGGUCCUGGACUCCCCGCACCAGAGGAGCCCAUCACUGUCUCUGGCCCCACUGUCUCCCAGGGCCCCAUCUGAAGACGUCUUUGCCUUUGACCUGUCUUCAAACCCCAGUCCCGGACCCAGCCCUGCCUGGACAGACUCUGCCUCCCUUGGCCCUGAGCCCCUGCCCAUCCCCCCGGAACCCCCAGCCAUACUCCCAGCAGGGGUAGCAGGGACUCCAGGGCUCCCUGAAUCCCCUGACAAGAGUCCUGUUGGUCGGAAGAAAUCAAAAGGCCUGGCGACCCGGCUGAGCCGCCGGCGGGUGUCAUGCCGUGAGCUGGGCCGGCCGGACUGUGACGGCUGGCUCCUGUUGCGAAAGGCACCGGGCGGCUUCAUGGGCCCGCGCUGGCGCCGCCGCUGGUUUGUGCUCAAGGGACACACGCUCUACUGGUACCGCCAGCCCCAGGAUGAGAAGGCUGAGGGCCUCAUCAAUGUCUCCAACUAUAGUCUGGAAAGUGGACAUGAUCAGAAGAAGAAAUAUGUGUUUCAGCUCACCCAUGAUGUGUACAAACCCUUCAUCUUCGCUGCUGAUACCCUGACAGAUCUGAGCAUGUGGGUGCGUCAUCUCAUUACCUGCAUCUCCAAGUACCAGUCUCCAGGCCGGGCCCCCCCACCCCGAGAGGAAGACUGCUACAGUGAGACCGAAGCAGAGGACCCGGACGAUGAGGCUGGGUCCCACUCAGCCUCGCCCAGCCCUGCUCAAGCUGGGAGUCCCCUCCAUGGAGACACAUCACCUGCAGCCACCCCCACACAGCGCAGCCCACGGACCUCCUUUGGCUCUCUGACAGACAGCAGUGAAGAGGCACUGGAAGGAAUGGUACGGGGGCUGAGGCAGGGUGGCGUGUCCCUCCUAGGCCAGCCACAGCCCCUGACCCAGGAACAGUGGCGGAGCUCUUUCAUGCGGCGCAACCGAGACCCUCAGCUCAAUGAGCGAGUGCACCGUGUGCGGGCGCUACAGAGCACACUCAAGGCAAAGCUGCAGGAGCUGCAGGUCCUAGAAGAAGUGCUGGGUGACCCUGAGCUGACAGGAGAGAAGUUCCGCCAGUGGAAGGAGCAGAACCGGGAGCUGUACUCAGAGGGCCUGGGGGCCUGGGGAGUGGCACAGGCUGAAGGCAGCUCCCACAUCUUGACCUCUGACUCCACAGAACAGUCCCCCCACUCCCUGCCCUCUGACCCUGAAGAGCACUCCCAUCUCUGCCCCCUGACCUCAGAGAGCAGCCUCCGACCUCCUGACCUCUGACCCUGGCCAGCACUCUAGCUCCUGACCUUUGACCCGAGGGCCACCUCAACCCCAGCUUCUGACGUGUCCAGGACAGAGCAUCCCUGGAUUCUGUUCAGGGUGGGAAGUAGUACUGCUAGUCAUGGUCUCACCCCGAGCUGACCCCUCUGCCUGGGCUUUGUGCCACCCUCUCCCUUGCCAAAGAAGAAACUCUCCCCCCAAAUCCUCCAACCUCUGGGGCCACAGCCCUGCCCCUCCAGUUCCUUGGCAGUUCUCCCCCAAACCAGGUCUGUACAGGUGUUCUUUAUUUUACAUGAGGGCUACUUUCCAACCAAAUAAAGUCAAUUUUUCUAAGAA